UUAUUUUUAUUUUUAUUUUUUGAGAUGGAAUUUCGCUCUUGUUGCCCAGGCUGGAAUGCAAUGGUGCAAUCUUGGCUCACUGCAACCUCCGUCUCCUGGGUUCAAGCGAUUCUCCUGCCUCAGCCUCCCGAGUAGCUGGGAUUACAGUCAUGCGCCACCAUGCCCGGCUAAUUUUGUAUUUUUAGUAGAGACGGGGUUUCACCAUGUUGGUCAGGCUGGUCUCGAACUCCCGACCUCAGGUGAUCCGCCUGCCUCGGCCUCCCAAAGUGCUGAGAUUACAGGCUUGAGCCACCACGCCCGGCCAAGAAGUUUUUAUUAUUUUUCUAGGGAUUUUUAUGGAACCAAUUGCAUUUUUUACAAUAAUCCUAAACCAUUGUUUUCUAGUGUAAACUGAUACAUUUUCUCACUGAGGGGGAAGACACCAAAAAACAUGAAGGUAUAAUCCAAAAUUGUAAAACUACUUUAAAAAAUUAAUUAUAAUUAUUUUGCUUGGAGAGCAAGCUAGAGGAGCUGUUUUCAGAAUUUUGUUACUAAAUGCCACUGUUGAAUGUGCCUUGAUUUCAUACAUGAUGAAAGAGCAAUUACUGGCCUAUGUUUACUAGCAGCUACUUUGCUUUACUGUUGGAAGAAACUGGUGGUGUUGGCGGUGAUAGAUUUGUAGUUGGCAUGUAUGAAGGAGAAGAGCUUGAUGACCUUUUGUUUGGGUUAUUGGUUAGAGAAGAAAAUAAUUUUUCAUUUAGAGUAGAGAUCAGCAAACUAUGGCCCAUGGAGGUUUUUGUAUGCCCCAUGAGCUAAGAAUUAUUUUUACAUUUUUAAUGCUUGAAAAGAAAUUCAAAAGAAGUAAUAUUUUGUGAUGUGUGAGAAUUAUAUGAAAUUUGGAUUUGUGUCUAUAAAUGAGGUUUUAUUGGAACAUAGCAUGUUUAUUUGUUUAUAUAUCUAUGGCUUCUUUUAUGCUAUAACAGUAGAGUUGAGUAGUUCCAACAGAUCAUCUACAAACUGAAGUAUAUGUUGUUUUGGCCCUAAGAAAAAAGUUUGCUGAUCCUGACUGUGCAGCCAAACUGCUCUCUAAUGUCUAGUCUUGUGCCUUAGUUUCCCUAUCUUGAAAAUGAGAAGAAUAAUAGAGCCAUGAGGUGAUUGUGAGGGCUAAAUGAGUUAGUAUACUUAAAGUGCUUAAAAAUAUACCUUGCACAUCAUAAUCACUAAGUAUUAGAAGUUAGUUGACAUUAAGUGUUAGAUUUAAUUGAUAAUCACUUUGUAACAUAGACUGGAAAAGAUGCAUUGAAAUCCAUUCUGUUGGAGAACAGCUACAAGUAUAUUAAGGAAGCAGGCUUUGGCUACAAUGUACUUCCAGAUCUUGAGCCAGUGGUGAAGGAGAUAGUGAAAGUUAUCAAUCCAAAACAAAACCUUUACAUUGCUGCACAAGGAAAGGAGUAUUGUAUAAAAGAUUGCAUUUUUACCUUGCAAAGUGCUAGCCAAAUUAUUCACUUGAGUUUUUAAAUGAAAUAAUAAGGUUACCUCGUGACUGUAAUAAUUCUGGUAUGACCAUUUCUGUGAUGCCAAGCGGCGUUUUCAAGAGUCCUAUUAGAAAUGUAUUUGGCAUCUUGAAUAGCUUGAACCUAUUACUCCUGGAUGAAAUUGCGCAAUUUUUAGUGUUAAGGAUAAGCUGUCAGAAUUUAAGAAGACUAAACUGUGGGGUAAAUGGCUCGGUUUCCCAGCUUGUUUCUCAACAUUUGGUUUUCUUCCCUUACUGGAGAGAAAACAAAGUGAAAUAUUUAUCCAUCUAGCUUAAAAAAAAUUGUGGUAAAAACACAUAAUAUAAAAUUUAUUAUCUUAACCAUUUAAAAAAUUUUUGUUUCAGAGACAGGGUCUCACUAUGUUGCCUAGGCUGGACUUGAACUCCUGGGCUCAAUUGAUCCUCCCCCCUCAGCCUCCUGUGAGUAGCUGGGAUUACAGUCAUAACCACUGGGUACAGACAUUUUAACCAUUUUUAAGUAUACUCUUCAGUAGUGUCAGUGUUGAAAUAUUCACAUUGAAAUUACACAAGUCUCUAGGAAGUUCCAAACUUUCCCAGAUCUUCUUGCUCACUUUGGACUUGAAAAAAUAAAACAUUAAAGUAGUCAGAUUUAUAGAAACACAAAGUAGGUGGUGGUUGCCAGGGCAUAGGGGAAAGGAAGUUGUUGUUUAAUAGAUAGAGGGUUUCAGUUUUGUAAAACGAAAAAGUUCUGCAGAUAAGUUGCAUGACAAUGUGAAUCACAAUUACAGGAAGGGUUUAUGAUCUAUUAUGAUCUGCUGGUAAUAAUUGUCAGCUGCUCUGGAAUCAGCUGAGAGUCCAGUGAAGUAAUCCAAGUAGAGUAGAGAAUAAGUUUAAACUAAGUCACCAGACAGACCGGUGUGUAUGCACUUUUACCCCCUUUGGGAAAAGUUAAACUGUUACAGCACAGCUGUCCUUUGUCACCCAGAAACCUCAAGAGUAAUCACUGGCAGGGCUUAUGCAUUUAGAUCAGAUAGUGGAAAAUAAAUGUGUAACUUUUGUAAUUUGAAUAGAAAAUACAAGUAUCGUUCAUCAGGUACUGGUUUCCAGUAUGUAAUGGUCACCUAAAUUUUUAUUUUGUUCAAAGUCUUUUCUCUGUUCAGUGCUCUUAAAAAAGAAAUUCUGAGCUGGGCACAGUGUCUCAUGCCUGUAAUCCGAGCACUUUGCAAGGUUGAGGUGGGAGAAUCACUUGAGGCCAAGAGUUUGAGAACAGCCUGGGCAACAUAGCGAGACACUGUCCCUACUUUUAAAAGGAAGUUCUACACUUAAUAUGUACAUCUUGCACAUUUCAGUGUGUUUUUGGCACCCAGUUGGCCACUGCUCUUAGCAAUAUAAUAGUAGGGGGAGAGAGUUUAUUUAGGUGUGUUUUAAGCAUUCAUGAUCUUUGACUCUUUUUGUAGAGGCAGAUCCUGUAGACCAUUCAGUGUUAAGUACUCUGUUUUAUCUUUUCCUAUUUGGCAGAGCCAUUAAUAUUUUCGAUGAAUUUGUCUAACACUGAGUAAUAAUGUUGGGGUUGUUGCCUUUCUGUCCACUUAAUUAAUAUCAAUCGUUUUUAUCUUAAUGUGGACUACAGUGAAUUACAGUGGAACUCUUUAUUUUUUGACAUUUUACAUUUGAAAAUGGAAUUGGCAGUGUGGUAUAUAGCAAAAUAGGCACUGAAAUAGGCAUAAGAAACCUCGCUUAAUAUUGAUAUUAAGAUGGGUGAUCAUGGCUAAGUCAUUAAAAUUCCUGUCUGGAAAUGAAGGUAUUGAACUAAAUAAUUUCCAGGAAUUCUGGUUUUUAUGACCAGUAUUUCAGAUGGAAACCAGUGUCACACAAUUUUUUUAAAUUCUCUGAGAUGUAUAUGUGUUUAUAUGUAUCAAAGCAGUUUGUGUUGUGUGUUUGAGAGUGGUUAUUUUGCUCAGAAAAGGCUAUUCAGAGUAUUUUGUUUUUCAUAAUGAAUAUUAGAUUUAUUAAAGCUAUAAAUUAAACAACUAGGAAUUUUAUUUUUAUUUUUUAUUUUUUAUUAUACUUUAAGUUCUAGGGUACAUGAGCACAACGUGCAGCUUUGUCACAUAUGUAUACAUGUGCCAUGUUGGUGUGCUGCACCCAUUAACUCGUCAUUUACAUUAGGUAUAUCUCCUAUUGCUAUCGCUCCUCCCUCCCCCCACCCCACGACAGGCCCUGGUGUGUGAUGUUCCCCACCCUGUGUCCAUGUGCUCCCAUUGUUCAGUUCCCACCUAUGAGUGAGAACAUCUGGUGUUUGGUUUUCUGUCCUUGCGACAGUUUGCUCAGAAUGAUGGUUUCCAGCUUCAUCCAUGUCCCUACAAAGGACAUGAACUCAUCCUUUUUUAUGGUUACAUAGUAUUCCAUGGUGUAUAUGUGCCACAUUUUCUUAAUCCAGUCUAUCAUUGAUGGACAUUUGGGUUGGUUCCAAGUCUUUGCUAUUGUGAAUAGUACUGCAUUAAACAUACGUGUUGCAUGUGUCUUUAUAGCAGCAUGAUUUAUGAUCAUUUGGCUAAGUACCCAGUAAUGGGAUGGCUGGGUCAAAUGGUAUCUCUAGUUCUAGAUCCUUGAGGAAUUGCCACACUGUCUUCCACAAUGGUUGAACUAGUUUACAGUCCCACCAACAGUGUAAAAGUGUUCCUAUUUCUCCACAUCCUCUCCAGCACCUGUUGUUUCCUGACUUUUUAAUGAUCACCAUUCUAACUGGUGUGAGAUGGUAUCUCAUUGUGGUUUUGAUUUCCAUUUCUCUGAUGGCCAGUGAUGAAGAGCAUUUUUUUAUGUGUCUGUUGGCUGGAUAAAUGUCUUCUUUUGAGAAGUGUCUGUGUAUAUCCUUUGCCCACUUUUUGAUGGGUUUGUUUGAUUGUUUUCUUGUAAAUUUGUUUAAGUUCUUUGUAGAUUCUGGAUAUUAGCCCUUUGUCAGAUGGAUAGAUUGUAAAAAUUUUCUCCCGUUCUGUAGGUUGCCUGUUCACUCUGAUGGUAGUUUCUUUUGCUGUGCAGAAACUCUUUAGUUUAAUUAGAUCCCAUUUGUCAAUUUUGGCUUUUGUUGCCAUUGCUUUUGGUGUGUUGGUCAUGAAGUCCUUACCCAUGCCUAUGUUCUGAAUGGUAUUGCCUAGGUUUUCUUCUAGGGUUUUUAUGGUUUUAGGUCUAACAUUUAAAUCUUUAAUCCAUCUUGAAUUAAUUUUUGUAUAAGGUAUAAGAAAGGGAUCCAGUUUCAGCUUUCUACCUAUGGCUAGCCAGUUUUCCCAGCACCAUUUAUUAAAUAGGGAAUCCUUUCCCCAUUUCUUGUUUCUGUCAGAUUUGUCAAAGAUCAGAUAGCUGUAGAUGUGCGGUAUUAUUUCUGAGGGCUCUGUUCUGUUCCAUCGGUCUAUAUCUCUGUUUUGGUACCAGGACCAUGCUGUUUUGGUUACUGUAGCCUUGUAGUAGAGUUUGAAGUCAGGUAGCAUGAUGCCUCCAGCUUUGUUCUUUUGGCUUAGGAUUGUCUUGGCAGUGCGGGCUCUUUUUUGGUUCCAUAUGAACUUUAAAGUAGUUUUUUUCCAAUCUGUGAAGAAAGUCAUUGGUAGCUUGAUGGGGAUGGCAUUGAAUCUAUAAAUUACCUUGGGCAGUAUGUCCAUUUUCACAAUAUUGAUUCUUCCUAUCCAUGAGCAUGGAAUGUUCUUCCAUUUGUUUGUGUCCUUUUUUAUUUCGUUGAGCAGUGGUUUAUAGUUCUCCUUGAAGAGGUCCUUCACAUCCCUUGUAAGUUGGAUUCCAAGGUAUUUUAUUCUCUUUGAAGCAAUUGUGAAUGGGAGUUCAUUCAUGAUUUGGCUCUCUGUCUGUUAUUGGUAUAUAGGAAUGCUUGUGAUUUUUGCACAUUGAUUUUGUAUCCUGAGACUUUGCUGAAGUUGCUUAUCAGCUUAAGGAGAUUUUGGGCUCAGACGAUAGGGUUUUCUAAAUAUACAAUCAUGUCAUCUGCAAACAGGGACAAUUUGACUUCCUCUUUUCCUAAUUGAAUACCCUUUAUUUCCUUCUCCUGCCUGAUUGCCCUGGCCAGAACUUCCAACACUAUGUUGAAUAGGAGUGGUGAGAGAGGGCAUACCUGUCUUGUGCCAGUUUUCAAAGGGAGUGCUUCCAGUUUUUGCCCAUUCAGUAUGAUUAUUGGCUGUGGGUUUGUCAUAGAUAGCUCUUAUUAUUUUGAGAUACGUCCCAUCAAUACCUAAUUUAUUGAGAGUUUUUAGCAUGAAGUGUUGUUGAAUUUUGUCAAAGGCCUUUUCUGCAUCUAUUGAGAUAAUCGUGGUUUUUGUCUUUGGUUCUGUUUAUAUGCUGGAUUACAUUUGUUGAUUUGUGUAUAUUGAACCAGCCUUGCAUCCCAGGGAUAAAGCCCACUUGAUCAUGGUGGAUAAGCUUUUUGAUGUGCUGCUGGAUUCGGUUUGCCAGUAUUUUAUUGAGGAUUUUGCAUCAGUGUUCAUCAAGGAUAUUGGUCUAAAAUUCUCUUUUUUGGUUGUGUCUCUGUCCGACUUUGGUAUCAGGAUGAUGCUGGCCUCAUAAAAUGAGUUAGGGAGGAUUCUCUCUUUUUCUAUUGAUUGGAAUAGUUUCAGAAGGAAUGGUACCAGUUCCUCCUUAUACCUCUGGUAGAAUUUGGCUGUGAAUCCCUUUGGUCCUGGACUUUUUUUGGUUGGUAGGCUAUUAAUUAUUGCCUCAAUUUCAAAGCCUGCUAUUGGUGUAUUCAGGGAUUCAACUUCUUCCUGAUUUAGUCUUGGGAGGGUGUAUGUGUCCAGGAAUUUAUCCAUUUCUUCUAGAUUCUCUAGCUUAUUUGCGUAGACGUGUUUAUGGUAUUCUCUGAUGGUAGUUUGUAUUUCUGUGGGAUAGGUGGUGACAUCCCCUUUAUCAUUUUUUAUUGCGUCUAUUUGAUUCUUCUGUCUUUUCUUCUUUAUUAGUCUUGCUAGUGGUCUAUCAAUUUUGUUGAUCUUUUCAAAAAUCCAGCUCCUGGAUUCAUUGAUUUUUUUUGAAGGGUUUUUUGUGUCUCUGUCUCAUUCAGUUCUGCUCUGAUCUUAGUUAUUUCUUGCCUUCUGCUAGCUUUUGAAUGUGUUUGCUCUUGCUUCUCUAGUUCUUUUAAUUGUGAUGUUAGGGUGUCAAUUUUAGAUCUUUCCUGCUUUCUCUUCUGGACAUUUAGUGCUAUAAAUUUCCCUCUACACACUGCUUUAAAUGUGUCCCAGAGAUUCUGGUAUGUUGUGUCUUUGUUCUCAUUGGUUUCAAAGAACAUCUUUAUUUCUGCUUUCAUUUUGUUAUGUACCCAGUAGUCAUUCAGGAGCAGGUUGUACAGUUUCCAUGUAGUUGAGUGGUUUUGAGUGAGUUUCUUAAUCCUGAGUUCUAGUUUGAUUGCACUGUGGUCUGAGAGACAGUUUGUUAUAACUUCUGUUGUUUUACAUUUGCUGAGGAGUGCUUUACUUCCAACUGUGUCGUCAGUUUUGGAAUAAGUGCAGUGUGUUGCUGAGAAGAAUGUAUAUUCUGUUGAUUUGGGGUGGAGAGUUCUGUAGAUGUCUAUUAGGUCCACUUGGUGCAGAGCUGAGUUCAAUUCCUGGAUAUCCUUGAUCACUUUCUGUCUCGUUGAUCUGUCUAAUGUUGACAGUGGGGUGUUAAAGUCUCCCAUUAUUGUGUGGGAGUCUAAGUCUCUUUGUAGGUCUCUAAGAGCUUGCUUUAUGAAUCCGGGUGCUCCUGUAUUGGGUGCAUAUGUAUUUAGGAUAGUUAGCUCUUCUUGUUGAAUUGAUACCUUUACCGUUAUGCAAUGGCCUUCUUUGUCUCUUUUGAUCUUUGUUGGUUUAAAGUCUGUCUUAUCAGAGACUAGGAUUGCAACCUUGUUUUUUUUGUUUUCCAUUUGCUUGGUAGAUCUUCCUUCAUCCCUUUAUUUUGAGCCUAUGUGUGUCCCUGCACAUGAGAUGGGUCUCCUGAAUGCAGCGCACACUGAUGGGUCUUGACUCUUUAUCCAAUUUGCCAGUCUGUGUCUUUUAAUUGGAGCAUUUAGCCCAAUUACAUUUAAGGUUAAUAUUGUUAUGUGUGAUUUUGAUCCUGUCAUUAUGAUGCUAGCUGGUUAUUUUGCCCGUUAGUUGAUGCAGUUUCUUCCUAGCAUCAAUGGUCUUUACAAUUUGGCAUGUUUUUGCAGUGGUUGCUACUGGUUGUUCCUUUCCAUGUUUAGUGCUUCCUUCAGGAGCUCUUGUAAGGCAGGCCUGGUGACAAAAUCUCUCAGCAUUUGCUUGUCUGUAAAGGAUUUUAUUUCUCCUUCACAUAUGAAGCUUAGUUUGGCUGGAUAUGAAAUUCUGGGUUGAAAAUUCUUUUCUUUAAGAAUGUUGAAUAUUGGCCCCCACUCUCUUCUUGAUUGUAGAGUUUCUGCCAAGAGAUCAGCUGUUAGUCUGAUGGGCUUCCCUUUGUGGGUAACCUGACCUUUCUCUCUGGCUGCCCUUAAUAUUUUUUUCUUCAUUUCAACUUUGGUGAAUCUGACAAUUAUGUGUCUUGGAGUUGCUCUUCUUGAGGAGUAUCUUUGUGGCAUUCUCUGUAUUUCCUGAAUUUGAAUGUUGGCCUGCUUUGCUAGGUUGGGGAAGUUCUCCUGGAUAAUAUCCUGAAGAGUGUCUUCCAACUUGGUGCCAUUCUCCCUGUCACUUUCAGGUACACCAGUCAGACAUAGAUUUGGUCUUUUCACAUAGUCCCAUAUUUCUUGGAGGUUUUGUUCUUUUCUUUUUACUCUUUUUUCUCUAAACUUCUCUUCUCACUUCAUUUCAUUCAUUUGAUCAAUCACUGAUACCCUUUCUUCCACUUGAUCGAAUCGGCUACUGAAGGUUGUGCAUGCAUCACGUAGUUCUCAUGCCAUGGUUUUCAGCUCCAUCAGGUCAUUUAAGGUCUUCUCUACAUUGUUUAUUCUAGUUAGCCAUUUGUCUAAUCUUUUUUCAAGGUUUUUAGCUUCUUUGUGAUGGGUUCGAACAUCCUCCUUUAGCUCGGAGAAGUUUGUUAUUACUGAUCUUUUGAAGCCUACUUCUGUCAACUCGUCAAACUCAUUCUCUGUCCCUUUGUUCCAUUGCUGGCGAGGAGCUGCAUUCCUUUGGAGGAGAAGAGGCACUCUGAUUUUUAGAAUUUUCAUCUUUUCUGCUCUGGUUUCUCCCCAUCUUUGUGGUUUUAUCUACCUUUGGUCUUUGAUGAUGGUGACCUACAGUUGGGGUUUUGGUGUGGAUGUCCUUUCUAUUUGUUAGUUUUCCUUCUAACAGUCAGGACUCUCAGCUGCAGGUCUAUUGGAGUUUGCUGGAGGUCCACUCCAGACCCUGUUUGCCUGGAUAUCACCAGUGGAGGCUGCAGAACAGCAAAUAUUGCAGAAUGGCAAUUGUUGCUGCUUGAUCCUUCCUCUGGAAGCUUCGUCUCAGAGGGGCACCCGGCUGUAUGAGGUGUCAGUCGACCCGUACUGGGAGGUGUCUCCCAGUUAGGCUACUUGGGGGUCAGGGACCCACUUGAGGAGGCAGUUUGUCCAUUCUCAGAUCUCAAACUCUGUGCUGGGAGAACCACUACUCUCUUCAAAGUUGUCAGACAGGGACGUUUAAGUCUGCAGAAGUUUCUGCUGCCUUUUGUUCAGCUAUGCCCUGCCCCCAGAGGUGGAUUCUACAGAGGCAGGCAGGCCUCCUUGAGCUGCGGUGAGCUUCACCCAGUUAGAGCUUCCUGGCAGCUUUGUUUACCUACUCAAACCUCAGCAAUGGCGGACGCCCCUCCCCCAGCCUCACUGCUGCCUUGCAGUUUGAUCUGAGACUGCUGUGCUAGGAGUGAGCGAGGCUCUGUGGGCGUGGGACCCUCCGAACAAGGCGUGGGAUAUAAUCUCCUGGUGUGUUGUUUGCUAAGACCAUUGGAAAAGCACAGUAUUAGGGUGGGAGUGUCCCGAUUUUCCAGGUGCCAUCUGUCACAGCUUCCCUUGGCUAGGAAAGGGAAUUCUCCAACCCCUUGCACUUCCCGGGUGAGGUGAUGCCCAGUCCUGCUUUGGCUUACACUCUGUGGGCUGUACCCACCGUCCGACAGGCCCCAGUGAGGUGAACCCUGUACCUCAUUUGGAAAUGCAGAAGUCACCUGUCUUCUGCAUCGCUCACGCUGGGAGCUGUAGACUGGAGCUUUUCCUAUUCGGCCAUCUUACAACUAAGAAUUUUAAACUCAACUCUUUACAGGUCUAACAUAUUUUAACAAUAAUUAAAAAGGUUUUUUUUAAAUAAAGACCUUAUCAAAUUGCACUUGUAAAUUUAGUAUUCAUUUUUAAGGAUUUAAAUUAUCUGACAAAUGUUUGCAAGUUGAGAGGCUAUAGAAAAAACAAACUCUUCUCCUACUAUGCUAUCACAGCACAGAACACUUCUGACAGCAGAUGUGUGGGGGUGUCCCCACACACCAAGCAGUCAACCAAUUUCUGCAGCAGGUGCUUCAGCAGAUACCAGCUGGGUAUCCUCCAAUUCAAUUCAAUUCUGACACUGUCUACCUGGAGAUACUAUUAAUACAAAGGAUACAAAUGAAAAGUUGCAUGAGGCAAGGCAUGUGGGAAGGGCCCUGGAGCUUCCAUGCUGUCUCUGGGCAUGCCACCCUCCAGAAACCUCCAUGUGUUAGGUAUCAUGAAGCUCCUGAGUCCAAGCCUUUUGGGUUUUUAUAGAAGCUUCAUUAUGUAGUCAUGAUUGAUUACAUCAUUUGGUGAUUAAUAUGGUUUGAUUUUGUGUCCUCACCCAAAUCUCACCUUGAAUUGUGAUAAUCCCCACAUAUCAACUGCAGGACCACGUGGAGAUAACUGAAUCAUGGGGGUGGUUCCCCCAUGCUGUUCUUGAGAUAGUGAGUUCUCACCAGAUCUGAUGGUUUUAUAAGGGGCUUCCCCCUUCGCUGGGUACUCACUUCUUUCUCCUGCUGCCCUGUGAAGAGGUGCCUUUUGCCAUGAUUGUAAGUUUCCUGAGGCCUCCCCAGCCAUGCAGAAAUGUGAGUCAAUUAAACCUCUUUUCCUUAUAAAUUACCCAGUCUCGGGUAUUUCUUCAUAGCAGCAUGAGAAUGGACUAAUACAGUAAAUUGGUACCAGGUAGUGGGGCACUGCUGAAAAGAUACCCAAAAAUGUGGAAGUGACUUUGGAACUGGGUAACAGGCAGAGGUUGGAACAGUUUGGAGGGCUCAGAAGAAGACAGGAAGAUGUGGGAAAGUUUGGAACUUCCUAGAGACUUGUUGAAUGGCUUUGACCAAAAUGCUGAUAGUGAUAUGGACAAUGAAGUCUAGGCUGAGAUGGUCUUAGAUGGACAUGAGGAACUUAUUAGGGACUGGAAUAAAGGUGACUCUUGCUAUGCUUUAUUAGCAAAGAGACUGGCGGCAUUUUGCUCCUGCCCUAGAGAUCUGUGGAACUUUGAACUUGAGAGAAAUGAUGUAGGAUAUCUGGUGGAAGAAAUUUCUAAGCAGCAAAGUGUUCAAGAGGUGACAGAGCAUAAAAGUUUGGAAAAUUUACAGCCUGAUGAUGCAAUAGAAAGCACAACCCCAUUUUCUGGGGAGGAAUUCAAGAAAGCUGCAUAAAUUUGCAUAAGUAACGAGGAGCCAAAUGUUAAUCACCAAGACAAUGGUGAAAAUGUCUCCAGCGCAUGUCAGAGGUCUUCACGGCAGCCCCUCCCAUCACGAGCCCAGAGGCCUAGAGGAAAAAAUGGUUUCUUGGGCGAGGCCAGGGCCUUGCUGCUUUGCACAGUCUCUGGACUUGGUACCCUGCAUCCCACCUGUGGUUAAAAGGGGCCAAUGUGCAGCUCAGGCUGUUGCUUCAGAGGGUGCAAGCAUCAAGCAUUGGUGCCUUACAUGUGGUGUUGGUCCUGUGGAUGCACAGAAGCCAAGAAUUGAGGUUUGGGAACCCUUGCCUGGAUUUCAGAGGAUGUAUGGAAGUGCCUGGAUGUCUGGGCAGAAGUCUGCUGCAGUGGUGGAGCCCUUAUGGAAAACAUCUGCUAGGGCACUGUGGAAGGGAAAUGUGGGGUUGGACCCAUCCCAUGCAGAGUCCCCACUGGGCAUGGCCUAACAGAGCUGUAAGAAGAGGGCUGCUGUCGUCCAGUCCACAGAAUGGUAGAUCCAACAGCUUGCACCAUGUGCCUAGAAAAGCCACAGACACUCAGUGCAAGCCCAUGUGCCAGCCAGGAGGGGAGCUGUACCCUGCAAAGCCACAGGGAUGGAGCUGUCCAAGGCCAUGGGAGCCCACGUCUUGCAUCAGUGACCUGGAUGUGAGACAUGGAGUCAAAGGAGAUCAUUUCAGAGCUUUAAAAUUUGACUGCCCUGCUGGAUUUUGGACUUGCAUGGGGCCUGUAGUCCCUUUGUUUUGGCCAAUUUCUCCCAUUUGGAAUGAGUGUAUUUACCCAUUGCCUGUAUCCCCAUUGUACCUAGGAAGUAACUAAUUUGCUUUUGAUUUUACAGGCUUAUAGGUGGAAGUGACUUGCCUUGUCUGUGAUAAAACUUUGGGCUUGGACUUUUGAGUUAAUGCUGGAAUGAGUUAAGACUUUGGGGGACAGUUGGCAGCACGUGAUUGUGUUUUGAAAUGUGAGGAUGAGAGAUUUGGGAGGGGCCAGGGUGAAAUGAUGGCUUGGCUCUGUGUCCCUACCCAAAUCUCACCUUGAAUUGUGAUAAUCCCCAUGUGUCUAGAGUAGGACCAGAUGGAGAUAAUUGAAUGAUGGGGGCAUUUCUGCCCUUCAGUUCUUGUGAUAAUCAGUGAGUUCUCAUGAGAACUGAUGGUUUUAUAAGGGGCUUCCCCGUUCGCUUGGUAUUCAUUUCUCUCUCCUGCUGCCCUGUGAAGCGGUGCCUUCUGCCAUGAUUGUAAGUUUCCUGAGGCCUCCUCAGCCAUGUGGAACUGUGAGUCAAUUAAACCUCUUUUCUUUAUAAAUUACCCAGUCUUGGGUAUUUCUUCAUAGCAGCAUGAGAGUGGACUAAUACAGUGUUCAGCUCAUCCUACAGCCCCUCUUCCCUCCCUGGAGGUUGAGAGUUGGGACUUCAGUCCAACCCUCUAAUCAGGAGGUUGGUUCCCCUGGAAACCAGCCCCGGCUCCUGAGGCUAUCCAGGAGUCCCCAGGCACCAGUCAAGCUAAUAGUGAACAAAAAGACACCAGUUUGGAGAUUCCAAGGAUUUUAAGAGUUUUUGCCAGAAAAUGGGGAUGAAGACCAAAUACAUAUUUCACAAUAUCAUACAGGCCCUUCCUUCUACCAUGAUUAUAGUAGCAGUUUAUUGUCCUGUGAUAGCUGCUGUUUUCAUUGUUCUGAAGAUGGUCAACUAUCGACUACACAGAGCACUUGAUGCUGGAGAAGUUGUAGAUAGGACUGCAAAUGAGUUCACGGAUCAGCGAACCAAAGCUGAACAAGGCAACUGUUCAACCAGGAGAAAAGACAGCAAUGGACCGAGUGAUCCUGGUGGAGGGAUUGAAAUGUCUGAGUUCAUCCGAGAGGCCACACCCCCAGUUGGUUGCAGUUCCAGAAAUUCUUAUGCCGGUCUAGAUCCAAGCAACCAGAUUGGAUCUGGUUCCUCGCGUCUUGGAACAGCAGCAACUAUUAAAGGAGAUACAGACACUGCUAAGACUUCUGAUGAUAUCAGUUUAAGUCUGGGCCAAAGUUCUAGUCUUUGUAAGGAAGGAAGUGAAGAACAAGAUUUGGCAGCUGAUCGGAAGCUCUUUCGUCUUGUCUCCAAUGACUCCUUCAUCUCUAUUCAGCCUUCCUUAUCCUCUUGUGGACAGGACUUGCCAAGGGACUUCAGUGACAAAGUGAACCUGCCAAGUCAUAACCACCACCACCAUGUUGAUCAGUCUCUGUCCAGCGCCUGUGACACAGAAGUAGCUUCUCUUGUACCUUUACACUCACACUCUUAUAGAAAAGACCACCGGCCGCGAGGUGUACCACGGACUUCUAGCUCUGCUGUGGCUUUUCCAGACACUUCACUGAAUGAUUUUCCCCUUUAUCAGCAAAGACGUGGAUUAGAUCCAGUUAGUGAGUUAGAAUCUUCCAAGCCUCUUUCUGGAUCCAAAGAAUCCUUGGUGGAAAAUUCUGGUUUAUCUGGGGAAUUUCAGCUUGCUGGUGACUUGAAAAUCAAUACUUCUCAGCCACCCACAAAAAGUGGGAAGAGCAAACCUUUGAAAGCAGAGAAAAGCAUGGACAGCUUGAGGAGCCUGAGCACACGGAGUAGUGGGUCAACAGAAAGCUACUGCAGUGGAACGGACCGGGACACUAACAGUACUGUCAGCAGCUAUAAAAGUGAGCAGACCAGCUCAACUCACAUAGAGAGCAUCCUGUCAGAGCAUGAGGAGUCUCCUAAAGCAGGAACAAAAAGUGGGAGGAAGAAAGAGUGCUGUGCAGGCCCAGAGGAGAAGAAUAGCUGUGCCAGUGACAAAAGGACUAGCAGUGAAAAGAUUGCUAUGGAAGCGAGUACCAACAGUGGGGUUCACGAGGCCAAGGACCCCACCCCCUCUGAUGAGAUGCACAACCAGAGAGGUCUCAGCACCUCUGCAUCUGAAGAAGCCAAUAAAAAUCCCCAUGCAAAUGAAUUUACUUCCCAAGGGGACAGACCACCUGGGAACACUGCAGAAAACAAAGAAGAGAAGAGUGAUAAGUCAGCUGUUUCUGUGGAUUCCAAAGUGCGUAAAGAUGUUGGUGGAAAGCAAAAGGAAGGGGAUGUUCGACCUAAAUCUUCUAGCGUAAUCCAUCGGACAGCUUCUGCCCACAAGUCAGGCAGGAGACGCACAGGAAAAAAACGGGCUAGCAGUUUUGAUUCAAGCCGGCAUAGGGACUAUGUUUGCUUUCGAGGUGUUUCUGGUACCAAGCCACACAGUGCUAUAUUUUGUCAUGACGAAGACUCUAGUGAUCAGAGUGACUUGAGUAGAGCAUCAAGUGUUCAGUCUGCUCACCAGUUCAGCAGUGAUAGCUCUUCUAGCACCACUUCUCAUUCCUGUCAGUCUCCUGAGGGCAGAUACAGUGCUCUAAAGACCAAACACACUCAUAAAGAAAGGGGCACAGACUCUGAACACACACACAAAGCUCAUUUGGUUCCUGAAGGAACCAGCAAAAAGCGUGCAACACGACGGACUUCUAGCACAAAUAGUGCCAAGACUCGUGCCCGAGUGUUGAGCCUGGACAGUGGCACAGUAGCAUGUUUGAAUGACUCAAACAGGUUAAUGGCACCUGAAAGUAUAAAGCCCUUAACCACUUCAAAAUCAGAUCUUGAGGCCAAAGAGGGAGAGGUGCUAGAUGAGCUAUCUUUAUUAGGACGGGCUUCCCAGUUAGAGACAGUCACUCGAUCUAGGAAUAGCUUGCCAAACCAGGUUGCAUUUCCUGAAGGGGAAGAGCAAGAUGCAGUCAGUGGAGCAGCACAAGCCAGCGAGGAGGCAGUGUCAUUUCGCCGUGAACGCAGCACAUUUAGGCGCCAGGCAGUACGGCGCCGGCACAAUGCAGGGAGUAACCCUACCCCUCCUACAUUGCUCAUCGGAUCACCCCUAAGCCUUCAAGAUGGUCAGCAAGGCCAGCAGUCCACAGCCCAGGUCAAAGUCCAGUCCCGCCCCCCUUCCCAGGCUGCAGUGCUCAGUGCUAGUGCCUCCUUGCUGGUGAGAAAUGGGAGUGUCCACUUAGAAGCAUCACAUGACAAUGCAUCUGCUGUAGGCGGUAGCAGUUUGCACGAUGAACUUGGUAAGUUCUCUUCUACGCUGUAUGAGACUGGUGGCUGUGAUAUGUCACUUGUGAAUUUUGAACCAGCAGCAAGAAGAGCAUCCAAUAUCUGUGACACAGAUUCUCAUGUAUCCAGUUCUACCUCAGUUCGAUUUUAUCCACAUGAUGUGCUCUCUCUCCCACAGAUUCGAUUGAAUAGACUAUUGACCAUUGAUACAGAUUUGUUGGAGCAACAGGACAUUGAUCUAAGCCCUGACUUGGCAGCUACUUACGGCCCAACAGAAGAAGCUGCCCAAAAGGUUAAACACUAUUAUCGCUUUUGGAUCCUACCCCAGCUGUGGAUUGGCAUUAACUUUGACAGACUCACACUUUUGGCCCUGUUUGAUAGAAAUCGUGAGAUCCUGGAAAAUGUGUUAGCUGUCAUCCUGGCUAUUCUCGUGGCCUUUUUGGGAUCUAUUCUUCUCAUACAAGGAUUCUUCAGAGAUAUCUGGGUCUUCCAGUUCUGCCUCGUCAUAGCCAGCUGUCAAUACUCACUGCUUAAGAGUGUUCAACCAGAUUCUUCUUCUCCCAGACAUGGUCAUAAUCGUAUCAUUGCCUACAGUAGACCAGUUUAUUUCUGCAUAUGUUGCGGUCUUAUUUGGCUCUUGGAUUAUGGUAGCAGAAACCUGACUGCAACCAAGUUCAAAUUAUAUGGAAUAACUUUCACCAAUCCACUGGUGUUUAUAUCAGCCAGGGAUUUAGUUAUAGUGUUUACACUCUGUUUCCCAAUAGUGUUUUUCAUUGGUCUCCUGCCUCAGGUGAAUACAUUUGUAAUGUACCUUUGUGAACAAUUGGAUAUUCAUAUUUUUGGUGGUAAUGCCACUACAAGCCUGCUUGCAGCACUUUACAGUUUUAUCUGUAGCAUUGUUGCAGUAGCCUUAUUGUAUGGAUUAUGUUAUGGGGCUUUAAAGGAUUCUUGGGAUGGCCAGCAUAUUCCAGUACUUUUCUCCAUUUUUUGUGGUUUAUUAGUGGCAGUGUCUUACCAUCUCAGCCGACAAAGCAGUGAUCCAUCUGUACUUUUCUCUUUAGUGCAAUCCAAGAUUUUUCCAAAAACGGAAGAGAAAAAUCCAGAAGACCCUCUAUCUGAAGUAAAAGAUCCACUGCCUGAAAAACUUAGAAAUUCUGUUAGUGAGCGAUUACAGUCUGACCUGGUAGUAUGCAUUGUAAUUGGUGUGCUGUAUUUUGCUAUUCAUGUAAGCACAGUCUUCACAGUAUUGCAGCCUGCCCUCAAGUAUGUGUUGUAUACAUUGGUUGGCUUUGUGGGUUUUGUAACCCAUUAUGUGCUGCCUCAAGUUAGAAAACAGCUACCAUGGCACUGUUUCUCUCAUCCUCUGCUAAAGACACUAGAGUAUAAUCAGUAUGAAGUUCGAAUCUUGAUUUAUACUGCCUUGUUAGAUGCAGCCACUAUGAUGUGGUUUGAGAAACUUCAUGUGUGGCUUCUUUUUGUGGAGAAGAAUAUAAUCUAUCCAUUGAUUGUUCUCAAUGAACUGAGCAGCAGUGCAGAGACAAUUGCUAGUCCAAAGAAACUGAAUACAGAAUUAGGUGCUUUAAUGAUCACUGUUGCUGGUUUGAAGUUGCUACGAUCCUCUUUUAGCAGCCCUACAUAUCAGUAUGUUACAGUCAUCUUUACUGUGCUGUUUUUCAAAUUUGACUAUGAAGCUUUUUCAGAGACCAUGCUGUUGGAUCUCUUCUUUAUGUCCAUACUCUUCAACAAGCUUUGGGAACUACUUUAUAAAUUGCAGUUUGUGUAUACCUAUAUUGCCCCAUGGCAGAUCACAUGGGGUUCUGCUUUCCAUGCUUUUGCUCAGCCUUUUGCAGUGCCUCAUUCAGCCAUGCUGUUUAUUCAGGCUGCUGUCUCGGCCUUCUUCUCUACUCCACUGAACCCCUUUCUGGGAAGUGCAAUAUUCAUCACUUCAUAUGUCCGACCUGUGAAAUUCUGGGAGAGAGACUAUAACACAAAACGAGUGGAUCAUUCAAAUACCAGAUUGGCUUCCCAGCUUGAUAGAAAUCCAGGAUCAGAUGACAACAAUCUGAAUUCCAUCUUUUAUGAGCAUUUAACUAGAUCCCUACAGCACAGCCUCUGUGGUGAUUUGCUACUAGGACGGUGGGGAAACUACAGUACAGGGGACUGUUUCAUCCUUGCCUCUGACUAUCUCAAUGCAUUAGUACACCUUAUAGAGAUAGGCAAUGGUCUGGUCACUUUUCAGCUGCGGGGACUUGAAUUCAGAGGUACCUACUGUCAACAACGGGAAGUGGAGGCCAUUACUGAAGGUGUAGAGGAAGAUGAAGGAUUUUGCUGUUGUGAACCUGGCCAUAUUCCUCACAUGCUUUCAUUUAAUGCUGCAUUUAGCCAGCGAUGGCUAGCUUGGGAAGUGAUAGUCACAAAGUACAUUCUGGAGGGUUAUAGCAUCACUGAUAACAGUGCUGCUUCUAUGCUUCAAGUCUUUGAUCUUCGGAAAGUACUCACCACUUACUAUGUCAAGGGUAUCAUUUAUUAUGUUACGACCUCGUCUAAGCUAGAGGAGUGGCUAGCUAAUGAGACAAUGCAGGAAGGACUUCGUCUGUGUGCUGAUCGCAAUUAUGUCGAUGUGGACCCGACCUUUAAUCCAAACAUUGAUGAAGACUAUGACCACCGACUGGCAGGCAUAUCUAGGGAGAGUUUCUGUGUGAUUUACCUCAACUGGAUAGAGUACUGCUCUUCCCGAAGAGCAAAGCCUGUGGAUGUGGACAAAGAUUCAUCCCUAGUGACUCUCUGUUAUGGACUCUGUGUUCUGGGACGGAGAGCUUUGGGGACUGCAUCCCAUCAUAUGUCCAGUAAUUUAGAGUCAUUCCUCUAUGGAUUGCAUGCCCUAUUUAAAGGAGAUUUCCGUAUUUCUUCAAUUCGAGAUGAAUGGAUCUUUGCUGACAUGGAAUUGCUAAGAAAAGUAGUAGUCCCUGGGAUCCGUAUGUCCAUUAAACUUCAUCAGGAUCAUUUUACUUCUCCAGAUGAAUAUGAUGACCCUACUGUGCUCUAUGAAGCCAUAGUAUCUCAUGAGAAGAACCUCGUAAUAGCCCAUGAAGGGGACCCUGCAUGGCGGAGUGCAGUACUUGCCAACUCUCCCUCCUUGCUUGCUCUGCGGCAUGUCAUGGAUGAUGGCACCAAUGAAUAUAAAAUCAUCAUGCUCAACAGACGCUACCUGAGCUUCAGGGUCAUUAAAGUGAAUAAGGAAUGUGUCCGAGGUCUUUGGGCAGGGCAACAGCAGGAGCUUGUUUUUCUACGUAACCGUAACCCAGAGAGAGGUAGCAUCCAAAAUGCAAAGCAAGCCCUGAGAAACAUGAUAAACUCAUCUUGUGAUCAACCUAUUGGCUACCCAAUCUUUGUCUCACCCCUGACAACUUCUUACUCUGACAGCCACGAACAGCUUAAAGACAUUCUUGGGGGUCCUAUCAGCUUGGGAAAUAUCAGGAACUUCAUAGUGUCAACCUGGCACAGGCUUAGGAAAGGUUGCGGAGCUGGAUGUAACAGUGGUGGCAAUAUUGAAGAUUCUGAUACUGGAGGUGGGACUUCCUGCACUGGUAACAAUGCAACAACUGCCAACAAUCCCCACAGCAACGUGACCCAGGGAAGCAUUGGAAAUCCUGGGCAGGGAUCAGGAACUGGACUCCACCCACCUGUCACAUCUUAUCCUCCAACACUAGGCACUAGCCACAGCUCUCACUCUGUGCAGUCGGGCCUGGUCAGACAGUCUCCUGCCCGGGCCUCAGUAGCCAGCCAGUCUUCCUACUGCUAUAGCAGCCGGCAUUCAUCCCUCCGGAUGUCCACCACUGGGUUUGUGCCUUGUCGGCGCUCUUCUACUAGUCAGAUAUCGCUUCGAAACUUGCCAUCAUCCAUCCAAUCCCGACUGUCGAUGGUGAACCAAAUGGAACCCUCAGGUCAGAGCGGCCUGGCCUGUGUGCAGCACGGCCUGCCUUCCUCCAGCAGCUCCAGCCAAAGCAUCCCAGCCUGCAAACAUCACACUCUCGUGGGCUUUCUUGCGACAGAGGGAGGUCAGAGCAGUGCCACUGAUGCACAGCCAGGCAACACCUUAAGUCCUGCCAACAAUUCACACUCCAGAAAGGCAGAAGUGAUUUACAGAGUCCAAAUUGUGGAUCCCAGUCAAAUUCUGGAAGGGAUCAACCUGUCUAAAAGGAAAGAGCUACAGUGGCCUGAUGAAGGAAUCCGGUUAAAAGCUGGGAGAAAUAGCUGGAAAGACUGGAGUCCGCAGGAGGGCAUGGAAGGCCAUGUGAUUCACCGAUGGGUGCCUUGCAGCAGAGAUCCAGGUACCAGAUCCCACAUCGACAAGGCAGUGCUUCUGGUCCAGAUUGAUGAUAAAUAUGUGACUGUAAUUGAAACUGGGGUACUAGAACUUGGGGCUGAAGUGUGAGCCAGUGUUUAUUAUAAAGACAUUUCUUUUUCCCUCUCAAUUCCAAGGCAUUGGAAAAAGAGAGGAACAAGCAGAAGAUGCCUGCAGGUAUCACUUUGAUCCUAUGUGGGAGCGACUGAAAAUAGAAUGAGCUUGGUUAAGCACCUCUCCUUUGCCCUUCACCCUGACUCCUGUCACUGUCUCCAUCCCCAAAUAAAGCUGAAAUAUUUUUUUAAGUUAGCUGCCGAGAAAACAUUUUGCAUGAAGGAUAAAGUUCUGUUAAAAUACAUCCUUAAAAAAAGUUUUUCCUAUGCAUUGCCUAUGCUUUAAAUCAACAAACUCUUCAUUUCUAAACUAUGAUCUCAUAUUUUUCUAAUUUCUUUGCCAAAAAUAAUUGCCAUGUUUUGUCAUAGAACAUGAAAUUCAUUUACCUUGAUUUUUAAGAACAGACCAGUGUAGAAAUGUUCCUUUUGACUUAUAGCAGUAUAAAAGUUUAAUGUACAGUGAAAGAGACUAUGAACAGACAUAGAUUUAUCUUAUUCCUUGAGCGCUAAAAACUUUAAUAAAAAAAACUGCACUAAUUUUUUACAGCAAUGCACUAAAGUCUGAGAUUUCUCAGAACAUUUAUUUAUAUAUAAAAAUAAAAUACCAUUAUUUAAAUUGCCUUUGGGAUUAGCCCCUUCCCUUUCCUUAUAAACACAGGUAGCAGGAACUGUGCUGCUCAUUUUUCUGUUAGUAGUGUGUACUUCAUGCCAGGACAUUGGGUAUUUUCUUUAAAGUGAAUAUAGAAUCUCAAGAUAUACGUAGCUUCAUCAUUGACAUUUCCCAGAGCCAAUAGUCAGCGGAUCGGUCUUGUGAACACCACUGCCAGCUCCUGUGUCUACAUCUCAGAGGAGCCCAUGUGCUCUGCUUCUCUCCACCAGAGCAAGCUCUGCUGGGCGUGCUUCUGGGAAGAAAACAAUUUUCUUUAAGAAGAAGAUGAAUGUCCAGGAAUUUAAAGAAAGGAUCGAUUGCCUUUUAUUUAUGAGUUUCUAGCUCUUGAAGUUAUUCACAUGCAGUUCAGUUAGUCAAGUAAAAUUUUUUUUCAAAUAAAAGUAUCCAAGUGGUGCAGUUAUUAUUAUAUCCCUCUUUAAUAAUUUUGCUUUUUAUUUUUCCCCUCUUCUUUUUCUGUUACUUGAAUUUUAUUUCCUGUAAUUUAUAGUGUGUAGCUGUAAAUUGAAAUAUUUAUAACUGUGAAAUUGACUUAAUUCAUAUGUUGUCUCAUAACUUUAUUUUUUUUAAAUGCAUAUUCAGGGAAAUAUAUUACUCAUAUUUACAAUUGGGCGAUAUAGGAACUUCAAUUUAGAUUUAAUUUGCAACUCUUAGCAUUUUUUAAAUCCUUGAUAAAAUUUUCCCUUUUGGUGUGAAACUCCAAAGAAAAUUGUACAUCUCCUCUGAGCAUUUAGGAGCAGCCAUCUUUCUACCCCUUGUGAAUAAAUCAUUGAAAGAAACAGGUAAAAUUAAUUUUAAUGAUACAUUUUGUUUCACCCAGUAUAGUCAAAGUAUUACUAUUUCAUCAUAUGUCACUAGCCAUAUUUCAAGUACUCAAUAGCUACAUGUACCUAGUGGCUACUGUAUUAGACAGUACAGAUUUAAAGUAUCUUUUGUUGAGGUGACAGAAGAGAGAAGCUGUUUUUCCUACCAAUUCUGAUGUAGAUCUCACAUUAUAGCAUAACAUUACAGUAGAAGGAAUGAAAACUAAGAAAGUAAAUAGUGAACAUACAGAACUUACUGCAUUUCCACUUUAAAACCUAUUUAUUUUCCCUUUUUCUAAUUUUAAACUUUUGUGGUCAUUCAGAACCUAAUGUGCCUUGUGUUGACAUUUCCAUAGACUUCACACUUUACAAAAUUUACUGUUUAAAAAUACUUGUCAAAUGAUUUACUGAACCUUUAUACAAAAGUACCCUUUCUAAAUUGACCAUUUAAAAAUGUAUUUUUGUGAUACCGUCAUUAUGUUCUGCAUUUGCCUCAUUUUGGCAGAUCUACAGUAUGCCAUUAAAGUUUAGUGUUGUUUUUGGUUUUGGAGGGUUUUUUUCUGAAACUGAAUUUAUAAUCUAUUUCUCUGUAUACGUAUAUUUUUAAAAUCUUCUGAAAGGAACUAUGUUCCCUGCUGCUUCUUCCCUUUCUGAAGUGAAUAUGAUCUUUUCAUGGUCAUUGCCUAGAUAAAAGUAGAGCCUUUUCAAUCUUAGAUGGAAGAUAAUUCAUUUUCCCACACAGAAAAAAAAUCUGACCUUUACAUGAUUUAAUCUGAAGGGCUAGAAUUUUUUAAUUUCUAGCCCCUCCUCCAAAAAAAUUUUAAACACAUCACAUACUCUGAAAAGUCAGAUUUCAAAUGCAAGACUAGACUUUAUAUGGAACAUAUAUGUUGGGUUUUGAUUUUGGGUAGCAAUUGACAUAUAUUUUUCUCAAAACAAGUUGAAUUUUGUUAACAUAUAUAAUUCUUUAGUGAAUUUAUAAAUUAGGAACCCUGAGAAGAAGCCCUGUUGUUUUUCUUAAGAGUCUAAAACUGACAAUCUUUUAAAAAUCAUAAUACUUUUCUAGUAAUUGCAUCAGGGAAUUGGUGAUAAUUGAAGAAAGAUCCAUUUCUUAAGAAUAAUUUGAUCUAAAUUAUUAUAUGGAAAUAAACAUACUUGUGUUAACUAAAUUGAUCAUAAAUUCUUGUUCCUGCCUCACCCCUCACCCCCCAGAGAAUAGUGAGUGACUCGUUUAGAUUCUCUGCUUUUUUUCAGUUAUGUACAAGACUUCAGCAUACAUUAAUGUCUUUAGUUUAUAAAUUUGCCAAUGCUUUAAUUUCCAUAAUUUGAAAGUUAAAAGAUGUAACUAAAAUACUAGCUUUUUUAUUCAUUUCCUUUUGGUGGAGUUGUAUGAUUGAAAACUUUGCUUUUUCUUGUUUAAUUCUUCCGCCACCCCCUCUUUUGAGAGAAAGGUAAUCGUGGAAUGAGUUAUAAAUUAUUGCCUUUUUUUCCUUUAUUUCUUUCAUUCAGUGGCAAAAAACAUUUUAUAACUCCUAAGUUUUUGGUUAAUCUUCCAACUUAUACCUUGGUGUGAACUCUCUUUUUACACCAUUUUCAACACUGGAUAAAACUUUAAUGUUGACUUUUUGCUAAAGAACUUUAAUUUUUCCAAGAAUCUAGAUUAACAUAAGAUGUUGAUAUUUAAGGAACUUGGAAGAGUAAGUGGUGAGGCUGUAUGUAUAUUUUUUAAGAGAUUACCUUUUAGGAAAUUAGUGAACAAACUUAACCAGUGUUCUGCCUUCUUUGACUUUGUUACUGGAGGAUGAUAAUCUAUUUCUAUUAGAUUCGAAGUAUUUUGGAAAAUAUUUCAAGUAUAUCUGAACUACUUAUAAUUCUUAAAACAGAAGUAGUCAGACAAUAUUUGUAUCCUAAGUGAGAUAUGGAAAAUUACUCUGUAUACUAAAUGUCAGGCAAUGAAAAUGUAAGUUUUUGUGUAGAAAACCCAUUAAGAAGAUGUGUUUUUCUUUCUGAAUUAGUUUAUUUUUCCAUCACAUACCAAAAUAUAAAAAUCAGCCUCACAUUUUUCAGCAAGUUUAGCUUAUAGCCUUGAUAAAUUCCUCUGUGCUUCUGAGCAGCAUCCUUCUGCCUCUGCUUAGCAGCUCUGCAUUUGGUGGAUUGCUGUUGUGAGUCAUUCAUCCAGCACUGGGCCUUUUAAGCUGAAGAUUCACCCAGUGUCUAAAGUUGUCCUUUUCUUAUAGCUAGCUUUCAAGCAUCUUUCCUCCUAAAUAAAUAUGUGACUUGAGAAAAAGGUAAUAAUGAUUUUGUCAGAAUUCUUUGAAUUUAUAUUUACUAGCUACUUAACCAUAAACUGCUGUCCAGAUUGUUAAUUUCAUUUAUAUUUAUUUUAAUUAAUUUGUCAUGAAUAUGGACAAAGCCUUUUCUGGGGUGUGUGUGUGUGUGUAUGUUUGUUUUUUAAGUCGUCAUUAUUCAUUCGUAUUCUUUUUCUGUGUAAUGUAAUCAUAUAAAGUUACUUUGGACAGAGACCCAGUUAAUUUUCUCUUUUGAUAGGAUACAUGGUUUAGAUAAGGUAUAAAGUGUCCCUUUUUAUUCUAGAGGCUUUUCCUUUAAUUCAGAGAUUAGUGGAGAUAAUAACGUCAGUCAAGGCUAAUGUGGUACAUGGAACUUGCUAAUGGAGGUUGGACAUUCUGUUUCAGUCUUACAUGGAUAUUGUUUCAUUGGUGUUGAGGAAGAAAAAAAUUAGAUACUACCAUGCAUUGGGACAGCAUAAUUCUAAUAUUACAUUGAAUAUGGCUUUUUAAAAAUAAGUAUUAAAAAGCCAAUCGUUUUCUCCAUUUAUCUAUCUUUUUUGUUUGUUUUUAAUUUGGUUGAUUGAUAUGCACCCAGGCCGUCUUAUUUUUACUUGUUAAAUGUCUGUCUAGGAAGAACUGUGAUUGGAAAGGAAUUAAUUAUUAUACAAAUAAAUCUGGUAGGAUAUGAGUGGAGUAAGUUUGCUUGAAACAGAAGUAUAUUUUCUACUUUGAAUCACCUCACCAGAGUCAUCUGUCAAGAAUUAUGUAUAACAAUUUAUCUUUAUUGCCUACAUACAACAUACUUUUUCUGAAUUAAGAUAACUUCUAUUUGUGAGUUGAACUUCAUUAUCUGCCAUUUUGUGGAAUCAACCUUACAUUCUUUGGUGGAACUAGAGCUGAUUGUCACCACAAGGUUAUAUGACAACUCUGUUCUAAGACUUAUACCUAUUAUAUAGGGUUAUACCUUUUUUCUUAUGCCUCAGCUCUGUACCUGACAAUUUAUGAUUCAGUGGAGCCAAGCUAGAAGGAACAAAGGUCAUCUAACACUGUGAUGGGGAUGAAUUCCUGAGUUUUACCUGCACAAUGAGGUGGUGCCCCGGAAUUCACAACAGAGUAGUGAUAGAGCAUAAGAUGGCUGCUCCAGAUGACUCUUGGGUUUAGUGUACUUGUGAUUGAACAAGAUUUUUUAUCUAUGAAGCUUGAUUCUACAACCAAAAUAAUAGAAAUGGGGGGGGGGGGGGGAAUCAUGUCUGCUUAUGCUUUUUAAAAGCUUAUAGUUUAAGUAAAAGUAAAAUGUAAAAACUGAUUAAACCUAUACAAGUCUGGCAAUGAGCUCUGCAUGAGGAAAUGGAAGGAGGAAUAUUGAAAAUGAUUCUAGGAAAGUGAACGUAAGAAAGGAAAAUGGGUUUUCCUUUUCUGAUCAUGGGCUCUGGAAAGUAUUCAUGGCCUUUACCAGCAUUCAGUAUAAACCAGAGAUAAGGACAUAUGUACUUACGUGUGUCUGUGAGUGUGUGUGUGUCUGAGUGUUAUUCUGAACAGCUUGUAAAUAUUGUAGUUGUUUAAAAUGGAAAAUAAAAGCUGAGUUCUUUUGGCAAAUAUAUUGCAUCAAAAAUACAGUAUUGACAGUGGAUAAAACACUGAGGAAAUAAAUUUUUUUUCAUUUUGC